AGACGCGCCAUGUGGGCCCUGCGGGCCGCCGUACGCCCGGGGCUGCGGCUCUCCCGCGUGGGCCGCGGCCGCUCGGCUCCGCGGGCAGCCGCGCCGUCCUGCCCCGCGCGCGCGCUAGCCGCUGUCGGCCGCAGGAGCCCCGGGAAUCUGGAGGGGCCGUGGGGCGGAGGGCGGGGCCUGCGGGCGGACGGCGGCCGAAGCCGCACGGGAGACGACGAGGAGGAGCCGGAAGAUGCGGACGAGAACGCCGAGGAGGAGCUGCUGCGGGGAGAGCCUCUGCUGCCGGCGGGGACCCAGCGCGUGUGUCUGGUUCACCCUGACGUCAAGUGGGGCCCGGGGAAGUCGCAGAUGACUCGAGCUCCUGUAGUCGAUGAGUGGUUUUUCUUUACGGGUGUUUUCCAAAAUGGCUAAUUCCUGGAACAGAUGAAGCCCCGAACUGCUCAGAACAGCGCGCAGACCUCUUGCCUCUCUACUCCCCAAACCUGCCGGUGGUUCCUCAGUAAUCCCCUGAGCACCCGCAGCUCCCGGGUUCCCUGCUGCGCCCGCCUGGAGCCCAAAUUCCAUCCGAGUGGCAGGUGGCGGAGGCCACAGCGCUGGUGCACACGCUGGACGGCUGGUCCGUGGUGCAGACAAUGGUCGUGUCCACCAAAACGCCGGACAGGAAGCUCAUCUUUGGCAAAGGGAACUUUGAGCACCUGACAGAAAAGAUCCGAGGGUCUCCAGACAUCACGUGCGUCUUCCUGAACGUGGAGAGGAUGGCUGCCCCGACCAAGAAAGAACUGGAAGCCGCCUGGGGCGUGGAGGUGUUUGACCGCUUCACGGUCGUCCUGCACAUCUUCCGCUGUAACGCCCGCACGAAGGAGGCCCGGCUUCAGGUGGCCCUGGCGGAGAUGCCGCUGCACAGGUCGAACUUGAAAAGGGACGUCGCCCACCUGUACCGAGGAGUCGGCUCGCGCUACAUCAUGGGGUCAGGAGAAUCCUUCAUGCAGCUGCAGCAGCGUCUCCUGAGAGAGAAGGAGGCCAAGAUCAGGAAGGCCUUGGACAGGCUUCGCAAGAAGAGGCACCUGCUCCGCCGGCAGCGGACGAGGCGGGAGUUCCCCGUGAUCUCCGUGGUGGGGUACACCAACUGCGGUGAGCACGCGCCCAGGGGAGGGGCCUUCCGCGGUCUCCGUGUCACCGGUGAGGACUCGCCCGGGGGAGGGCAGGGGGUCCCUGUCGUCUCAGUGGUGCCGUACGACAGCUGCGGUGAGCACGUGCCCAGGAGAGGGGGUUCCCAUGGUCGCCGUGUGGGGUACACCAGCUGCUGUGAGAGCUCACCCAGGAGACGGGUUUCCUGUGGUCUCUGUGUGGGGUACAGCAGCCAAGGAAAGACCACGCUGAUCAAGGCACUGACGGGCGAUGCCGCCAUCCAGCCACGGGACCAGCUGUUUGCCACGCUGGACGUCACGGCCCACGCGGGCACGCUGCCCUCACGCAUGACCGUCCUGUACGUGGACACCAUCGGCUUCCUCUCCCAGCUGCCGCACGGCCUCAUCGAGUCCUUCUCCGCCACCCUGGAAGACGUGGCCCACUCGGAUCUCAUCUUGCACGUGAGGGACGUCAGCCACCCCGAGGCGGAGCUCCAGAAAUGCAGCGUUCUGUCCACGCUGCGUGGCCUGCAGCUGCCCGCCCCGCUCCUGGACUCCAUGGUGGAGGUUCACAACAAGGUGGACCUCGUGCCCGGGUACAGCCCCACGGAACCGAACGUCGUGCCCGUGUCUGCCCUGCGGGGCCACGGGCUCCAGGAGCUGAAAGCUGAGCUCGAUGCGGCGGUUUUGAAGGCGACGGGGAGACAGAUCCUCACUCUCCGUGUGAGGCUCGCAGGGGCGCAGCUCAGCUGGCUGUAUAAGGAGGCCACAGUUCAGGAGGUGGACGUGAUCCCUGAGGACGGGGCGGCCGACGUGAGGGUCAUCAUCAGCAACUCAGCCUACGGCAAAUUCCGGAAGCUCUUUCCAGGAUGAACGGACGCCCACAGAGGCCUGCGGGGUGGGGGCAUCGCUGCCUGGGGAGCUGAGGCGUUACCGCUGUGUUGGGGGCAGCUUGGUGUCAGGUGCAGCAGGGUCCUCCUUGUCUGGUUCUGCACCCGUCUCGCUCCCAGCCAUUUGCUGGGAUGACCGUGCAGGCCGGUGACACGGCCGCACCUGCCCCAAAGCGGGCCGCCCGAGCGUCCACUCCAAGCCUGAGCAUCCACACAAUUCCAGUGGGCCCUCGGUGCCUGCUGUGAACUGCUUUCCCUCGGAAUGUUUCCGUAACAGGACAUUAAACCUUUGAUUUUA